AAGACAUAAGCUGAACCUCUGGCCUGCAGUUCCAGAUCCAAGGUGACUGAGACAAACUGCCAGCUGCCACUGGCUUAUCAGGAGCACCUGGGCUAUCUUAGUUUCCACUGCUGCAGCCUGUGGCCUGGACAUUUGCCCAUGGUUGUGAGGUCCCCAUGCAUGGGACUUCUUCCUCCUGACUCCAGGCUUCAGUUCACCCAUCAGGCCUUAAAGCAUCUUCGGCCCUAUCUUGCCCUGAACUUUUUGCUGCAAAAACCAAGGGCACUGCCUCAAGCUUAUCUUCCCAGCCACUGUUUACUGCUGCUACAUUGUUGCCCAAGACACUUCAGAAGUGACUGUUGUUGUCAUCUCCUGCCAAGUCCUGGAAGGCAAGCCACCAAGUCCCAUGCACCAUUCCCACAGCCCGACAACCUUCCUGACUCUACCCACUGGAAUCUAAAGAGUCUGCCCACUUCUGGAUGUUUGUUCAGAAUCUGCUGACACAUCAAGGCCACUUUUCUUAGGAGCCCCCUGACUUCCAAAAUCAGUGCCUUUGGAUUCAUCUCUUCCGGGAGAGUUCAGUGUCUUCUGAAAUGUUACAAAACGUCCUUCAGAGCAAGAAGGCGUACACGAGGAGCUCGACUCUGUAGAAAGGAGAUGGACAACAUGUCUCCCAGGCUGAGAGCCUUCCUCUCCGAACCCAUUGGAGAAAAGGAUGUCUGCUGGGUGGAUGGCAUCAGCCAUGAGCUCGCGAUCAAUUUGGUCACCAAAGGUAUCAAUAAGGCCUACAUCCUGCUGGGACAAUUCCUUCUGAUGCACAAGAAUGAAGCCGAGUUUCAGAGGUGGCUCAUUUGCUGUUUUGGUGCCACUGAGUGUGAGGCCCAGCAGACUUCUCACUGCCUCAAGGAGUGGUGUGCCUGCUUCCUGUAGACACAAACCUCAUUGCUGCCCCCCACCACCCUCUGGGGAAAAUGACGCCUUCUCCACCUA